AGAGGCGCGGGCGGCUGCGAGGCCGGCGGACGCACCGGCCCGAGGGAACGCGCCGCCGGCCGGACUUGGCCUGGCUCCCGGAGCCGGGGCGGCGAGCGCGGCGGGCGCAGCGGGGCUGGAGGCUCCGGGCAGGCGCGGGGGAGCGGCGGCGGCGGCGGCGAUCGGAGCGGCGGCGGUGGUCUCGGCGGCGGCGGCGGCGGCGGCGGCAGGGAGCGGGCUCCCGGUGCCGGGCACCGGGCGGGCGGCGGGGAAGAUGACCGCGGGCGCCGGCGUGCUCCUUCUGCUGCUCUCGCUCUCCGGCGCGCUCCGGGCCCAUAAUGAGGAUCUUACAACUAGAGAGACCUGCAAGGCUGGGUUCUCUGAAGAUGAUUACACGGCAUUAAUCUCCCAAAAUAUUCUAGAAGGGGAAAAGCUACUUCAAGUCAAGUUCAGCAGCUGUGUGGGGACCAAGGGGACACAAUAUGAGACCAACAGCAUGGACUUCAAAGUUGGGGCAGAUGGGACAGUCUUCGCCACCCGGGAGCUGCAGGUCCCCUCCGAGCAGGUGGCGUUCACGGUGACUGCAUGGGACAGCCAGACAGCAGAGAAAUGGGACGCCGUGGUGCGGUUGCUGGUGGCCCAGACCUCGUCCCCGCACUCUGGACACAAGCCGCAGAAAGGAAAGAAGGUCGUGGCUCUGGACCCCUCUCCGCCUCCGAAGGACACCCUGCUGCCGUGGCCCCAGCACCAGAACGCCAACGGGCUGAGGCGGCGCAAACGGGACUGGGUCAUCCCGCCCAUCAACGUGCCCGAGAACUCGCGCGGGCCCUUCCCGCAGCAGCUCGUGAGGAUCCGGUCCGACAAAGACAAUGACAUCCCCAUCCGGUACAGCAUCACGGGAGUGGGCGCCGACCAGCCCCCCAUGGAGGUCUUCAGCAUUGACUCCAUGUCCGGCCGGAUGUACGUCACAAGGCCCAUGGACCGGGAGGAGCACGCCUCUUACCACCUCCGAGCCCACGCUGUGGACAUGAAUGGCAACAAGGUGGAGAACCCCAUCGACCUGUACAUCUACGUCAUCGACAUGAAUGACAACCGCCCUGAGUUCAUCAACCAGGUCUACAACGGCUCCGUGGACGAGGGCUCCAAGCCAGGCACCUACGUGAUGACCGUCACGGCCAACGAUGCUGACGACAGCACCACGGCCAACGGGAUGGUGCGGUACCGGAUCGUGACCCAGACCCCACAGAGCCCGUCCCAGAAUAUGUUCACCAUCAACAGCGAGACUGGAGAUAUCGUCACAGUGGCGGCUGGCCUGGACCGAGAGAAAGUUCAGCAGUACACAGUCAUCGUUCAGGCCACAGAUAUGGAAGGAAAUCUCAACUAUGGCCUCUCAAACACAGCCACAGCCAUCAUCACGGUGACAGAUGUGAAUGACAACCCGCCAGAAUUUACCGCCAGCACGUUUGCAGGGGAGGUCCCCGAAAACCGCGUGGAGACCGUGGUCGCAAACCUCACGGUGAUGGACCGAGAUCAGCCCCACUCUCCAAACUGGAAUGCCGUUUACCGCAUCAUCAGUGGGGAUCCAUCCGGGCACUUCAGCGUCCGCACAGACCCCGUAACCAACGAGGGCAUGGUCACCGUGGUGAAGGCAGUCGACUACGAGCUCAACAGAGCUUUCAUGCUGACAGUGAUGGUGUCCAACCAGGCGCCCCUGGCCAGCGGAAUCCAGAUGUCCUUCCAGUCCACGGCAGGGGUGACCAUCUCCAUCAUGGACAUCAACGAGGCUCCCUACUUCCCCUCAAACCACAAGCUGAUCCGCCUGGAGGAGGGCGUGCCCCCCGGCACCGUGCUGACCACGUUUUCAGCUGUGGACCCUGACCGGUUCAUGCAGCAGGCUGUGAGAUACUCAAAGCUGUCAGACCCAGCGAGCUGGCUGCACAUCAAUGCCACCAACGGCCAGAUCACCACGGCGGCAGUGCUGGACCGUGAGUCCCUCUACACCAAAAACAACGUCUACGAGGCCACCUUCCUGGCAGCUGACAAUGGGAUACCCCCGGCCAGCGGCACCGGGACCCUCCAGAUCUAUCUCAUUGACAUCAACGACAACGCCCCUGAGCUGCUGCCCAAGGAGGCGCAGAUCUGCGAGAAGCCCAACCUGAACGCCAUCAACAUCACGGCGGCCGACGCUGACGUCGACCCCAACAUCGGCCCCUACGUCUUCGAGCUGCCCUUUGUCCCGGCGGCCGUGCGGAAGAACUGGACCAUCACCCGCCUGAACGGUGACUAUGCCCAACUCAGCUUGCGCAUCCUGUACCUGGAGGCCGGGAUGUAUGACGUCCCCAUCAUCGUCACAGACUCUGGAAACCCUCCCCUGUCCAACACGUCCAUCAUCAAAGUCAAGGUGUGCCCAUGUGAUGACAACGGGGACUGCACCACCAUUGGCGCAGUGGCAGCGGCUGGUCUGGGCACCGGUGCCAUCGUGGCCAUCCUCAUCUGCAUCCUCAUCCUGCUGACCAUGGUCCUGCUGUUUGUCAUGUGGAUGAAGCGGCGAGAGAAGGAGCGCCACACGAAGCAGCUGCUCAUUGACCCCGAGGACGACGUCCGCGACAACAUCCUCAAGUAUGACGAGGAAGGCGGUGGCGAGGAGGACCAGGACUACGACCUCAGCCAGCUGCAGCAGCCGGAAGCCAUGGGGCACGUGCCAAGCAAAGCCCCUGGCGUGCGUCGCGUGGAUGAGCGGCCGGUGGGCGCUGAGCCCCAGUACCCGAUCAGGCCCAUGGUGCCGCACCCAGGCGACAUCGGUGACUUCAUCAAUGAGGGACUCCGCGCUGCUGACAACGACCCCACGGCACCCCCCUAUGACUCCCUGCUGGUCUUCGACUACGAGGGGAGCGGCUCCACCGCAGGCUCCGUCAGCUCCCUGAACUCAUCCAGUUCCGGGGACCAAGACUACGAUUACCUCAACGACUGGGGGCCCAGAUUCAAGAAGCUGGCGGACAUGUAUGGAGGUGGUGAAGAGGAUUGACUGACCUCGCAUCUUCGGACCGAAGUGAGAGCCGUGCUCGGACGCCGGAGGAGCAGGACUGAGCAGAGGCGGCCGGUCUUCCCGACUCCCUGCGGCUGUGUCCUUAGUGCUGUUAGGAGGCCCCCCAAUCCCCACGUUGAGCUGUCUAGCAUGAGCACCCACCCCCACAGCGCCCUGCACCCGGCCGCUGCCCAGCACCGCGCUGGCUGGCACUGAAGGACAGCAAGAGGCACUCUGUCUUCACUUGAAUUUCCUAGAACAGAAGCACUGUUUUUAAAAAAAAAAAAAAAAAAAGAAGAAAGAAAGAAAAAAAAAAAAAAAAGAAAGUGCCUUUUGGUACAUGUAUCAGAUUCCCUCAAACUCAGGAGUGUCUAAAGCAGACAGACCGUCCCCACCUUCCCAUCCCGAGCGGCCUCCAACCCCAGCUAGUCCCAGCUCUGAAGGCAUCAUUCAGAAAUGGGGGAGACUGUGUCUGUCUUUCUUACUUUUUUUUUGGUCUUUUAUUAAGAAAAAGAAAGUGGGUGACUUGUUUGAAAACAGAGUGGGGUUCAAAUCCCAGCAGCCUUUGCUGUACACAGCUGGGGGUCUCUUGAGCCUCUUGGGAGUCAAGGCCAGCUGGGAGGCUUAGCCCUUCAGCCCCAGCAGAAGGCCCUGGGGCUGGUGGGGCUCAGAAUACCCCUACCUUGUGGCUGCUCCCCACCCCUCCCGGAUGCUGUGAGGAGCUCAGGCAGGGGCCUGGAGGGGAACAGGGGUCAUCCUGAAGGGGCUCCACCCCCAGUCAACCCAGGCCUCCCUCAGGGACACCUGUCACCCUGAGUGCCACCAGGUCCCCUCUGCCUUUGGUCCAGAAGAGUGAGUUGUCCAAACCAGCCAGCAUCUGGCUCCAGCCCUCCAACCCUGGCGACCAGACCCCAUGGGGUGCCAUCAACGGCCCCGCGACAGGCAUCAAUUCAAACCCCAGGACACUCUCGACAGCUCCAACCAUCCGGAGGGCUGUGCAGAUGGCAGGAACCAAGGACCCUCCCUGGCAGCUGAAGAGGGCAGUUACGGUUGGGCGUGGUGACCAGAACACACCCAGCAGCCUGCGAAGCCUCCCCGUCCCCAGCCUGUGCUCCUGAUUCCCGCCAGACGCUUGUGAGCCUGUGUGGGUGGCAGGAGGCCCCGUCUUGCCGUGCCUACCUGUCGCACAGAUGCCUCUGCACGCUGCAGACGGUGCCUCUCCUCUCCUAUGGACCCUCGUCGGGGGCAGGCAGCGGCCGGGUCCAAACUUGCUGCUGUCCUCGAGGCUGGCACUGCUAUCUCCAGGGCUGGGUUGACUCAAGCCAGACAGGGGGAAGGAAUUGGUUCUGCAGGACAGUGAGAGGGUCUGUGUCCCGGCACCCCUGGGACAGCGCUCGGCUGCCUGUGCUCACUGCAUGAGAAAACUCAGAGGGUGCAUUCUCCCUCUGGCAUGGCUGUGUCUGGGCGCCUUGGGCUGCGGCAGGGGGCAGGCCCCACGUGGGGAAGCCUCGUGCUUGGUCAGCUUUCUGUCUCUCCCAGGCCAGUGACAACUGGCUUCCCGAGGAAGGAGGUGAGGUACCAGGGACCCUGGGCAGGACCUGGUGUCGGGCAGGGCGGUGCCAGCACUGGGGAAGGACAGGGAGCCCUCCCGGAGCCCCACCCUGCACCUGCCACUGGGGUCAGGGAGUGUCUCGGGGUGCCUUUGGGGGCAGCAUGAGCUCCACCAGGGGCCCCGGCCCCCACCUCAGCCUAUGGCCCUUCCCCAUGGCUAAGGUCAUGCCUUUUCUGAACAGCUUUGGCCUUGAGUGCACACAUCUGUGCCAGGCUCACGGCAUGUUCCCGUUGGAUGUCAGGGUCCUUGUCCAAACCAAACUCACAGCUGCCCCUGUGCAGCCUUCAGAGUUGAGCUGGGGUCUCAGUCUCCAACCUGUCCUUUCUGACCCUCCCAUGGCUGCCCAGGGAGGGCGGGGUUCACUGUGCCACGUGCUGGGUGCCCCCCUCUGCAGACAGCCAGUCCAGGAGAUGGACCAACAGAGGUCAAGGGGCAGCUGGCCAGGCCGCACCGGGGUCCCCGAGUUCUGAGCUGUGCUAUGCAAACAAGAAUGCUCCUGUGUGGGGGGGCAUGGCCGUUGGAGGUAUAGCUGGGCGGGUAGUGGAAGGACUGGAAAUCUCUGUUGUUGUUUGGGGAAGUCCAUGCUUCAGUCCUUCGGAGUAUGCGUGGAUUGUUCGAAGUGUGACUAUGGCCCGGGAGCCAGGGCAGCAUGAACUCCUUUCUCUGAAAUUUCGAGGCCUCCUUGGGUUCCCUGAACUCCGGGCUGAUGUUCCCAGGACCCAGCACCAGGAGACCCCAGUCCCGCCAGCAGCCGCCGCUACCCAGGAGGGCUGGGCGACAUUGGCCGCCUCCCACUAGCUCCCCCUCCUCGCCCACAGCCUCUUGUCACUGCCAAGCCCCCGUUCCUUUUGCCCAAAUCACGCAGGCGGAAGCUGCAGUGCCAGCUGGAGGGAUGUUCAUAGGGCUUCCUGUGCCCAUCCCUGCUCCAAACAGCUGGACAGCUUCCCCUCUACCCCCACCCUGGUGAGCCCCUGGGGGCCAGAGAAAGAUGGGGUUCCUGCACCUUCCCAGCUCCACCUCUGAACUUGAGUUAGCGUUAGCUAAGCAUACAAUCAGUGUCGAACGUCUCUCUUCCUUAAGCUUGUAGAUACGACUGCCUAUAAUCAGGGGACUCCCACUGGAGGCCGGGAGGCCAAUGCUGGCCAGGUGCGAGGGCAUGGUUUGGUUCCUUUAGGGAAUUUUUGUUUUGCAAACAGGAGAAACCUGUGCUGCAGGUUGGAGUGGCAGGAACGACUGGCCUUGGUCAGCAGGCAGCCCCCAGCCUAGGGCCACAGUCCUCUUCAGGGCCUGGGCAGCCCCAAUUUCUGGCCCAGCAGGUUUCUCUUUGUAGUGUCUUUCAGCACAUCCAAAAUGCUAGGCCUCCUGCCACCAACGUGUCAGAGCAAUGUCCAACUGUCAGGCUCUCAGAGAUGCCUCAGUUUCCCUAGCAUGAGCACCAGCCGACACACACAGUCCACUGAGAUGAUAAUUCUGUUCUCUCCAAAGCAAAAAGCUGGGCGAGGGGUAGUCUCAAUUUCUGUCAGUGCUCAAAGGAAUAACACCAAAAGAAUCAACACAGAAUCUCCCAGACACACGUGACCCAGCUCGUGGCGCCGUGGGUCCGUAGGAGGGACAGUACCUCACAACAGGCCCAGCGGGGGACCACCUCUCUGUACAAUUGGAAUGCGUUUUACUUUUCUUUUCUCUCCUUUUUUCAUUCCGAUUUUUUUUGCAUGUUUCUUUUUGAAAUGGGCAAAAUGUGUAGCAGCCUGCAUGAGCACAGUUGUUUUGGGGAAAGAUACUGGAGUAUGAUGUACUCACACCUGCAAAUCUGAGCAUCGCGAGGUUAAACGUUCCACCUUUUUUUGUAAUCGUCAACAGCACAACUAUUUUGUAUUGUUGUUUGUAUCAUUUUGUACCAAAAAAAAAAAGGAAAAAAAAAGGGAAGAGAGUUGAUGUUUUCAGUGUGUUUCCAGUGCCAGACAGUCUUGGUCCUGAACUCAGUAGACCCUUGCGGAGCGGUUGUGCGCGGGCAGGCGGGGCGCGCUGCUCCAGAGAAUGAAUAAAGUCCCCCUUUUCCGUA